CUCCUCCCUCUAAUGCCUGUAACUCACAUCCGAGGCUGGGCGAGGAAUCCGGAGGGGAGAUUUUCCUCAUGCUCACGGUUGUUGGAAACUGGAAGAGUGAGAGGAAGGAGGAAGGGGAUUUGUGGCGCUCUCUACCUACUACAAGACUGACAAGGGGAGGGGGCACCUAAAUUUGCAUCUUUUCUUCGUGGUGAUUGAGAACUGCAGGUUCAAACCGAUCCCACUGAGCACUGGCGAUUGAUUAUAAAAAAAAAUCGACACUGGGAGAAGGGAGGCUCUGUCUUCGGCUGUCAGACUCAAUCUCGGAGGUGGUAUUGGUGUGUGAGUGUGUGUGGUGGUGUUUUUUUUUCUUUUUUUUUCUUUUUUCUUUCUUUCUUUCCUCUUUUUUUUUUUUUCCUUCUCUCCUAGGGGCUACACAAUGGCAGUCUUCUCUCAGUAAGAUGAAUCCUGCUUUGCCUUCUGCAGAUCCACCCAUCCUCAUAGCGAUCAAGGUGUCUAAGCUGCUGGAUUGCUUUUCGCCCAAAUCAAUGUGGUUUCUUUGGAACAUUUUCAGCAAAGGAACGCAUAUGCUGCAGUGUCUUUGUGGCAAGAGUCUUAAGAAAAACAAGAACCCAACUGACAGGAAGAGGAAUGUCAAGGAGAUUAAGUGAUUUGUCCAAGAUUAUACCGCUAAAGAGAGGCUGAGCUGAGACCAACAGGCCUGUCUCAUGAGCAUGAGUAAGAGCCAGCCGGGCUGAUGUUAACUUGUAUAAUCUUAUGCUCUGGAAGGUGUGCGUGCCACGAAUCCAAUAAGGAGCACAUUAGUAAAUGCAACUUGCAGACAUCAUGUGAAGUGACUCUUGAUGCCAAGAGAAGAUCCCCAGCUCAAGGGUAUAGUGACCAGGUUAUAUUGCAGGCAAGGCUACUACUUGCAAAUGCACCCCGAUGGAGCUCUCGAUGGAACCAAGGAUGACAGCACUAAUUCUACACUCUUCAACCUCAUACCAGUGGGACUACGUGUUGUUGCCAUCCAGGGAGUGAAAACAGGGUUGUAUAUAGCCAUGAAUGGAGAAGGUUACCUCUACCCAUCAGAACUUUUUACCCCUGAAUGCAAGUUUAAAGAAUCUGUUUUUGAAAAUUAUUAUGUAAUCUACUCAUCCAUGUUGUACAGACAACAGGAAUCUGGUAGAGCCUGGUUUUUGGGAUUAAAUAAGGAAGGGCAAGCUAUGAAAGGGAACAGAGUAAAGAAAACCAAACCAGCAGCUCAUUUUCUACCCAAGCCAUUGGAAGUUGCCAUGUACCGAGAACCAUCUUUGCAUGAUGUUGGGGAAACGGUCCCGAAGCCUGGGGUGACGCCAAGUAAAAGCACAAGUGCGUCUGCAAUAAUGAAUGGAGGCAAACCAGUCAACAAGAGUAAGACAACAUAGCCAGAUCCUCACAGGUGUUGUGACUUAUUCGUCCUGAGCACAGUUGAGUGAUUUAUCCUCACCAGACAUUCCUGCUCCGUGGCUGAAGAGCAGCAGGAAGUAAGCUAAUGCUUAUUCUUUGCUGUCUCCGAACUUCUCUGUUGCAAGUGGAUAAAUCUCAACCUGUUGCACCCCCCACAACAAGAAGACACCUGGAUAACCAGCUAAACUCAGACCAUGGAAUGCCCUACCAGAUAUGGAAUGCCUUUUUAAUAUCUUUUCUGUGACUGUGACACUUCAUGUGAAUGACAUACUUCACAAGUACACUCGAUACCUUGCCUGCUGACAGCUACCCAUAAUCCUUUUUGAGUCCUGUUUCAGCGAAAUCUAUGUGUUUAAGUUCAAUUUUGUAGCACACAAAUAAUAUUGAGUAAUUUCUAGUUAGACGCUGUAAACCUGUGCUAUUACGGAUUUCUCUUCUUCCCAUUUUUACAGGGCUGCUCGCUCCACUGUCUGUGACCUUUUGCAGGGAUUUUGUUCCUCUAAAUCUUAAAUGUUGCAGUUGGCUUAGGUCGGAGAGCAAUCAGGGAAUCAGGAAGCCUUCUAAACCUAUUAUUACAAAUUGCAUCUAUAAAGAAAGAUUAAGAAAGAUUGUUGUCUCUGGCUCACACUAUCGAUUAAACACACAUAUACGCUCUGUCCAGUAGCAGAUACUGUGCUCCCAAGGUCGGCAUUGCCUGGGUGGGAAAUGGCUCAAACACAAUCCAGGGAAGCUCUCUAUGAUAUGUGUUUGACAUCCCCCUCUAGUUUCUUUGUGUGUGUGUGUUUUAUACAUAUCACAAGCUUACUGGUAAUGGUAACAUUUGCCUUGCCCAGCGAGCAAGACCCACUGGUUUUUGAGAAAGUGGGUCCAAAGAUUUCUGUAGGCCUUGUAGGCCUGAUUAAGGUUCAUUUUUCAUCUAUUAAUUCUCAUUAUUUGGAAAAAAAAAAAAAGGAAAAUCAGUAAUUAUAACCUACAAGAAUUGCGCUACCUAAAUCCAUUUCAGAUAUACUCCGUCCUGUUUUUAAUGAACCAAACUUAACGCCAUCCCCGUUUCUGGCUGCGUUCCCCUCAUACUCAGCAGAGCAUGGGCAAGACGGCUGUUGUGUUCUUUCCUGCAGCAGCAAUGCAAACGUUAGUUAUAAAUUAAUUAGACUUUAAUAUUUUUGGUGUUUAAUGACAAGUUUUUAAACUGGACAUAUUAGGAAAAAUAUUUUUUUUAGCUCAGCAUGCUGAGUCCGGUACUGUGUAUUUCACCAGUACAUGCCUCUAGCUCAGCAUCUGGGGCUCAUGUUGCCCAGUGGCUGGGUUAGAGGUGCCUUGCCAUGAUCUCAGAAUACAGUCUGUUGAAUUAUCCUAGAUGAAAAUAAAGGCAAACCAACACAUUCAUCCAUGAGGAUUUUGGUCCAUUCCAUUUAUUUUCUUUUAUUUUGCAUUCUUAAUUUCCUUUUUAGUUUAACACUGUUUGUUUGAGCUUAGGGAAGACAACUACCAAGAAAGGCCAGGAACAGUUGACUACACAAUGAAGAUUCCAUGCAAAAUGUUCAAUAUUGGAUCUAAAGGGGUUCAAAAUGUUUCAUACUAAACUGUUUGGGAAUUUAUUUGUUAACUCUGUGUACACCUAAUAAAAUUCAAUGUUUUCUUCUCAGAAGAGUUCAUUGAGACCAAACUGAACCUCAUUUAUUGAAAAUUAUAUGUGGGAUCAAUGUACUGGCCUCUUGUUAUUCUUUCUAUGUGGGAGGAUGACCCAGUCAUCAUUUUCCCCAUCUGCACUGUAUUUAUUGGGAAAUUAUUUUGUCACUGCUUUCAUAAAUCUUCUUCAUGACAGCCCUUGCCCAGCAUUAAAAAAUUCUGGCCUGCUUAGCUGAUUAAAGGUUUAGUAGAAAUUUAACUGUUUGUUUAUGCUUAUUUCAUUUUCAUAUUGGAUUCUACUUGAAUAAAUAAAAAGUUAGCAGAACGUUUGAGUAGAUUUAUUGCCAAUGAUGCUAAAUUACAAAUCUAACAAACAAAAUGAUUCCUUUGGUCAUUUUUGAUUUGGUGUUAUGUCAUCUUGAAGCCUAUUGUUUUUAACAGGAACAGUUAAAAUAUAUUAGAUAACUUCCAUUAACCAAUUAUUUUCAGAAAACAUAGAUCCCAUAAUAUGUGGCCAACUAUAUGAGUAAUUAACUAACUUGUAAUACAGUCAAAUGGGCUUAUGGACACUACUUACAGCAGCAACACUUCACUUCACACAAACACACACAUAUACACACACACACACACACACACACACACACACACAGAGCAAACACCCCCAUCUAUUUGUUACUGAUAAUUAGCCCUACUUGCUGGUUUCUUUUUCCCCUGCAAGUCUGUUUAUUGGUUUAAAUUAAGACAAGAUUUAUUUUUGUAAAUGACUGAGAUUUAUGUAAAUGUGUAUCUCUGUUGUGUUUUAUAUAUGGGGUGUCUAUAAGGGCAUUUAUCCCUAUGAAGGAUGUCAAAUACUUUCUUCUAAUAUAUGUUUAGACAUAUUGCAGAGGGGUCCUUGUUAUUUGUAAUUGAGUUAGGUCAUUUACUUUGUGUCUGGUCUCACCUGUAGCAUGGGAAGAGGACAGCAAUGAUGAGCUGCAUGUAGUAGGUACCUGUGUAUCAAGAACUGUUGGUAUGUAUUGCUAAUUUGCAUACAAAGAGUUUGUCUGUCUGCAUUGUAGUUUGUGUUUAAUAUCAUUUGUUAAAUUCACAAAUACAACAUAUUGAAUAAAAUAUUUAUAUGAAGGCAUAUUAAAAAACAUCAAACAACUUUAUGUAACAAAAUGGCAUUGCAUUACUCACCAAUAUAGAGAAAUGUCAUGUAAAUAAGUUGGUAAACUCAAUUUCCCCCUUUACCAUGCCAAAGAAAAUUUUAGCUCUUUGAUGAUACCUCUCUUGCUAUUUGUUUGGGAUAAGACUUCGCCAUUUUUUUCCCCUCAGAAAUUAAGUUUGCUGUUAUUAAGUAAGAAGUGCAAUCUGUCACUACUGAUGUUCCGUAUAGUAAAUCUGAUGGAAUUCAUUUGUAUUUAGACUGUGUGUUUUGUACCUCCAUGUGCAUAUGUCCAUUGUAUCAAGUCUCUAUAAUACUCCAUUCCUUCUGCAUGCAUAUCUGGUGUGGGAGGGUUAUUUCUACUGAUUUGUUAUAGUAGCUGAUUGCUUUGCCAGUCCCUCAACAACGCUCAGAAAUGUUGUUUUGGUAUUUCAAGUGACAACAUUUUUGUUUUCUAAUAUAAGAUUGCUUUUUAAAACAUUUUGCUACCACUUUACUUGGAAAAAUUAGAGAAGACAUGACAAUUCUCCACCCUAUGUAAAGAGCAAAAUGGAACUGAACAUCAUUUCAUUACAAAUCCUGAAGAAUUUGGAGAUUCUUGCUCUAAAUGUUUGCUUGUCCUGAAUGUUUUUGGGUAGCAGUGGCUUAAAGAGAUCCACGAUGGGUCCAAAGGACUCCCGCUCCAGUUCUUCUAAUAGUUUGCCUCUUGGGGAGCAAGCAGAAGUUCUUUAUCAUACCUAGCCACUUGCUUAAUUAAUGCUUUAAGCACUAAAAGUUGUUAUUUUUAUCAGGAUGAACAAUAUCAGAUUUGGUUGUCUUUAAAAGCAAAAACCAAAAACUUAUUCUUUAAGUAAGUUAGACACGUAUCACUUCAUUUAAAAUUAUCUCCCUAAUAUUAUGGAUCAUUAAUAUUUGAUACAUAUUCAAAAAGAGACCACAUUGACUAACAUCCAGUUGAGAACAAGAUGAAAAUAAUUGAAAUAUUUUUUCCAUUUUAAUUCAGAACAAGGCUAUAUCAAGGGAAAGCGACUGGGCUAAAUCCUCAAUUUUUUUUUCCAAAAUGCAGGCAUAUCAAAAUCCAGGAUGUACAUGGUCUUACUUUGAGUGAAAUAGUAGUCAUAGCUGAGGUUUCUUAGCCUACAAUGUGACAUAGGGCCUGUUGACUCUCUUGAAUAUGGAGUAGGGUUUCAAAGUGUUGACAGUUGAGUCUGCAAACUAAGGCUGAGUUAUAUUUUAGUUUUUUUUUUUUUUCCUGGUUUUCACUAAGUCUAAUUCCAAUGUCUACUGGCAGAGAUUGUGUUUGCAUUUGAGGUAGUGGAGGGCGGUACUUUCCAAGUGCUGUUGGAAUCCAGAUAAACUCAAGGAGCCCAGAAAGACAACGGGUAUAAUGGCUCUCCUCUUAUGACUUAGCACUUUAGUUGACUUUUUUGAAAAAGUCUCUGGGUGGAAUACCUCAGUGAUGAUGAUUUGCCAAACAAGCAGCGUUAGUGCCAACACCUUCUCUAAACUUGCUGCAUCCCUUCCAAUUGACAUUAAUCCCACUGCAACUUCCUAAAAACAGGAAUGAGCCAAUGAGAUUUGCUUAUUUUCUCUCACCCAUUACAAGUAAGUUUGUUCUUGCCCUGCUUGUUUUUUAGAGGGAGUUUCUAUCAUAGAGUUGAAAAUCACAUUUAAGAAGGAAAGAGUUUAUGUCUUUACAUGUAACUAUUUUAUUUUUUCCAAUCUAAAUUCAAUCACUUCUUAAUAGAUAUAUUGGUGUUUGCAUUGCUGGCAUCAAAACCACACAUACACACACAAACACACACAUACACACAAACAUAGUGGACAGAAAUAAGUAAAAAUAUUUCUGUUUUCAAAGAAAAAGCAUUCCUUAGAGUUUAGGUACCAUUAACUUCUACUAUAAUACAGUUCCGGUACUAUGGUUUCUAACUAAAUGAACACUAGAACAGAGCUGACUAUAUUUUCAUCUUUGUCCAAAAUUUUAGAUGAAUCACAUUUUGAACUUUUUAUGGUAUGAUAAUUUCUCCAAUAUCUAAAUUCUUUUUCUGAGAAAACAAAUGCCGAGGACAUUUUUGACACUCUUCUUACAUGAGACUAUGAAAAAGAGCAGCACUUUUGUUGUAGUUGUUGUUGUUAAUAAAAAGGAUAAUAACAUACAGAGGAUUAUAAGAAAAAUAAGACAUACCUGAGGUUUUGUGAUGAGCUAUAGAGAAUCAAGGGCAGUUCCAGUGGAGCUGAGGCUGACAAAGUACUGCCCAGCUGCCAGCCAAAUCCACCCUUAAGUUGCUUUUGUAUGGCCUGGGAGCUCAGAAGGAAUUUUUUAAAUUUUUUUUACAGCUUUAAAGUAUUAAACAGAAACCAACAAAGAAGAAUAUGAGACAGGGACGUACGUGGUCCGUAAAGUUUAACUUUCUGAUCCUUAAUAGGAGGAUAAGCGCCGUGAUAGAGAAAUCCAAAGGUCAUUUGUAUUACGAUGGCUAGAUAAUGUAAUGAAUUCCAAUGUCUGUGCAUCAGCGAAUACGUCAUCAAAAUUGCUACAAAACAAUAAUAAUAGGUUGUUCACAGCUUAAAAUGUUUAGGUAGUGAAGAGGAAAGAAUAUAACCUACAUUAUUUAUUGACUACUUAUAUUUCCCUCAUUUUACGGAAGAGAUCUAUCAAUUUACGUACUCAAUAAUAGAACUACAACAUGGUUGCACUCCUUAAUCUCAGGAUAGAGAUAACAAUUUUUAUAAAUCUAUUACAUUAUGAGAACAUUGUUAGUACUAUAAAAAUCAGGAUCAGUUAAAUGUUCUCUUAAAAUAAUUUUCAAUAUUAAAUUUUUAAGUAACUCAGUGGAUGCAUAUUUUCCUUAUUUUUGGAAAUUUGACUUAUAAAGUUUAAGCCAUGACUAGAAUAUUUACAUCAUUAAAAUAAAAUUUCCAAGUAAAAAUUUUCAUCUUAAAGUAAUACGGAAAUGAUUUUGCUACAUUAUUCUAGGAUUUUACAAAGUAAUUCACCUUUAGAAAAAAAGUGGUUUUUUUUUUAGCUCUAAAUAAUUAAAGGUUGCCUAAACUAAUGUGUAUAAGUAGAUUUACCUGUAAAUAUGUAAGGGAAGUCCCAAUUAUUGUACACUUUCAUAAUUCAAUGUGAAUUUCAUACAAAGCAAAGUUUCACCAUUAAGAAAAUAAACAUUUUGUUCCUAUCACUGAGUGAAUAUUUGUAAUUUCUAUUUAAGCCAUUUCUAGAUUUUUUUUUUUUUUUGGUCUUUUGUGAGCUUCUGAGAUUGGUGCCAUUUUAUCACAGUAUUUCUCGUCUUGACUUCUUUGCAUGACCCCAGGUUUCCAGUAAGUAAGGUAUCCUUAGAAAAAAAAGUAUUUUAAGGGAAAUGGAUGCAUACUUCAGGCCCAUUUUAUAUGUAACUCAAUAUUGUCUUUUUAAAAGGCCACACUACCAUGGAAUAAAUUAAAAUAAAAAAUCAGAUUUCUUGUACGCAUAACCCCUGCCCAGUUUUAAAAAUGUGAUCCCUUAUUUCUAGAAACCUAAAAUAGAUAUCCCUGAAUAACAAUUCAUUUUUAAUUAUCAGUAGAUAUAUAUACUGACACAGAGUAUAAACAACUUCUGUCACUAUUUAUUUAAAAUGUUAAAUUGUACAUUUUUCAUAAUUUCUUUAAGAGAAUCUUCUUUGGUGAGUUUAAAGUGAGAGUAGACAAAUAACUUAGUGGCUAAAUGAUUUAAUGUCAGAUGACUUAAUGACCAGUUUUUGCCCUUGAUCCAGCCCCACUCUGAUAUUCUACCUCCUGUGUGCUUGUCUUCAUUGUCCCCAUAUUAAAAUGGUGACUGAUACGGAAUUCUGGAAAAAUCUGAUCGAUUAAUUAAUGUGAAUAUGCAUGUUUUCCUUAGAUUCUAAUAUGGUCUUUCUUGUGUAAGAAUGUGGAUUUCUAAUAGCCAUAUAACUCAAUGUUUCUCAGUUUGAGCCCUAUUGGCAUUUGGGGCUGGAUAAUUCCUUGUUUGGGGGCUGUCCUGUACACUGCGGGAUGCUCAGCAGCAUCCCUGGCCUCUACCCACCAAAUGUCUGCAGCAUACCUUCCUACCCGACCCAGUGUGACAAUCAAAAUUGUCUGUAGAUGUUGCCAAAUGACUUUUGGGUGGAAAAAUUGCUCUCGUUAGGAACCACUUAUGUUAAUUAUGGAAGAAUCUUUUUUUUCUAAUGUUAUUUGCAUCUAAAUUUGCAUAACUCAUUUCUAAUAGGUACUCGGAUUUCAUUCGUAAUUCAGAAAUAGAAAAACAUACAAUGGUCUUUUUAACCUGUCCUAGUGGUGAAUAUACAUGGUUUCCUUCGCAUUUAUCUGUUCUAAUGGCCCAGAAAAAAUAAGAAUCCAGACCUCUCUCAUGUAAUUGUUAAGGAUAUUCUGAGCCAAGCCAGAUUUCACAUGCAUUUCCAUUCCAUCCAUCCCAGCAUUCACAGUUUCCACAGCUACAUAUUCCAUUCCCUGCAAUAAAAUACAUAUAGGUAUCAUGAUUAUGAUCAAAAUGUGCCAAAUUUAAACAUGCUAUUAUAAAUCACAAGUGUCCACAAUGAAAUCAUUUCAUUCAUCCUUGGUAGAUUUUCUUAUUGUGCAAUGAUGUUAUUAUUACAUCUUAUUAAGCAGCUGCGAGACAUCUAAUCUUUCAAACAAUUAGUGGCAUUUAUUUGGUGCCACCCUUUACCGAUCAGAUAGUCACCAUCCUGUAUCACUCCAGCUAGGCUUUUAGGUGACAAUUUUGUUUUCCCUUAAAGAGCAAGUUAUAUCUGACUUAUGAAUAAAUACAGAAAAACAUAAGGCUCUUUGACAUAACAUGAGGCAGGCCAAGUAAUCCGUGAAGAGAGUCUUACGUAGUAAGGAUGGGCAGAAAGCAAAGGUCUAACUUAAUGACACACAAAGAGUCAUCUUUUACCUUCAGCUAGAGCUGAGGAGAAGUAUACAUGUCUCUGUUUCCUCGUAACUUGGCUAAACAAAUGAAUUUAUAACCAAUUAUGAGGACUCAAUAAAUUAGGAUAGCAGUGGCUAUGACACGGCUGAGCCCUCUUUAUACCUCUCCCCCAUACACACAUCCAGUUCCCUAAAAGCAACCAACACAUCAACUAGUGGUACCCAGAUUCUGUUUAAAAGAAUAUUUCAUUCCCUAUACCAUGUUCAAAGUAAAAUGGUUGCCAACAAAAUUCUUUUCUGUGUUCAAUAUACAACUGCAUACAUGUGAGUUUGAGGGUGGGGAGGUUACUUUGUGGAAGGAUCCCAAAUAAUCACAAAAUUUAGCUUCAUUCUCUUGUAUUCUUCUAUGCCUAGGAAUAAUGUGAGGCUUUUGUGAGGGCUUUUUCCCAAAUGCCCACUUCGCCUUUGGUAGAUAUUUCAUAUUCACGGUUGGCCCUGUUGGUCCAGCCACCUAAAGCAUUGCAUGACGAGUGUCUCUUGGCUCUAUAACAAACUGUGGCAUAGAGCAAUUAGAAAAGGUUAAUACUGCACCUGUACAAAUGAGACCAUCAUGUUUGUCGCAGUCUCUGUCAUCACAGUCACAGAACUCCCCAGAAAUAUACCACUCUUCAGCAGAACAAAUGCACUUCCCACAAUGACAAGAACCUGAAAUUACAAAGGCUAUUACUCACCAUCACCUUAUAACUAAAGGUUUCCAUCUCGAAUAGAAUAUCGUUGACACACUGACAACAGGCUUCUAAUAACCCAUCAUCCAAAGGUAAAAGUGUAUUGAAUGGCUGGUUUCUCAGAGGGGAGCUUUACUUACUGUAAUUCAUAAAGGUCACCCAGGAAAGCCUUCAUUAUGGAUCUAGACAGUUGCAAUUAGCCUUGAACAAAUGUCCCAUGGCCCAGUCUGGUUGAAAUGUCAAUGAGAGCAGGAUGGGGUUGAUUCUUAUAGAUGGUCUUCCAAAAAAGUAUUCAAAAAUAGAUUUUUUCCUCCUAAAUUGAAUCAUGUUUUUAAAGUGCCUGCUCUUUAAAGGAAAUGAAUAGGGAAUUGUAUUAAAUUAGGUUGCAUUUCUAAUUAAAACAACUACUAAAUUAUUGUGCUUAUAAUUUUGGAUUUUCGUUUACAUGAUUUUCUUGGAGUAGGAGCACACCUGCAUAUUGGGUGGCUAAUUAAAGUGCUAAAAAUGCAUACAGUCACUCAGUAUAUUUGCCUUGUGAGACUCAUCCUCAGGACCCUCUGUCAUAAACUGGGAUAGCUCAAAUUACUCCCAAAGUUCAUAUUUUAUGAGGCUCUGGAUUCAACUCUUUUUCCCUCCACUUCACCCAUUUCUCCUACCUAACUAAAAAACUUCCUCUUUGGUUAUUUAAAAUAUCUUUACUUACUGAGUAAAAAUUUUAUUAAUGAUAUAUUUAAAAUAAAAGAAAAUAAAUGAGAUGAUGAAUGGUAUCCAAGACAGAAGUUCUCUCAGUCUAAACAGCUUUCCAUGACAGACUAAAAACCCUUACAUGGAAAAACUGCCUCAACGACAGCAGGAAAGACUUUACAAUGAAAAAGAAACAAAUAAAAAGGACUUUCUUUUCCUUCUGUUUCCUUGGGUUGGUUGUUCUUUCCAAACAUGACUUCCAUUUACUAAAAGAUGGCUGUAUUCUUUUUGAGUCAAAAUCACGUUGAAAAAAUGUGCAGUUGAAAAGAGUAUUUUGACAUAUUUAACAAAACUGCAGAAUUGGUAAGUUCAAAAUAUAUUGAAAAGGGGCAAGAAUCAAUCAUUAGUGCUUCUUUUAAAACACAGUGAUUAAAAAUGAGUUAACAGCCUGGGUGAUUAAAGUGAUCAGGAAAAAGGAGUUGUGGUCAUCACAGAUAUCAUGAAAGGAUUCAGGUUCAUGUGUCUCAACUAUGUGAUAUUUCAUAUCAGGGAAACUGGUAUAUGCAUUUCAGCUGCAAAAAUCCCCAAAGUCCAAAUUAAAUGUUUGCCAUUUCUUGACACACUUCUCAAAGUAAGAGUGCAGUCAGAAUUAUUUAGAUUGUGACAAUUGUGUUUUUUAACUUCUUGCGUAGCUAUGGCAUAAUUGUAUUUAGUCUUGACUUGUUUUCCUGAGGGUCCAGGUUGAUUUGCAUGCUCUUGAGGAAAUAUACACGUCUUCUCAGUUUUAAUAAUUGACUGACAGCCCUGUGGUUUCUCAGGACCCAGUGAGCUGCUGCUCCCAGGUCAGUCUGCAAAGGAUGCUGGUUCCCUUGUGGUCUCAUCAAGGUGAGGAAUUUCCUGAUUUUAGAGAUUUCUUUAUCCUAAUUUUGAAGACUUUCUUUCACAUUUCUAGGCAUAAAAAAAUGUACAGCACUCUACUGCUUGUUUAACAAAUGGAUAGUGAUAUAUCUGCCAACAAAGACCACAUGGAGUAUUUCAUUGACUAUCAGAGAAGUUUCCUCGAAAGGCACCAUACUUAGUGUUUUAUUUCCAUGAGUGAAGGAAAAUUAGUUAUUUGAAGUAUUUGGCUGUCUUUAGUUGUUUCUAAAGUAGUGCUGAUUUUAUAUGCCCAUAAUAUUCAUAUAUACACCCAGGAUAUCAUUUUAUAUAUGUCACAAUUCAUGAAAUAUCUUAUAUUUCAUCUUCAAACUUAUCCUCUGGCCCUGGAACUAUUCUAAUCACUGCUCUUGCUUCUGGAAUGCUUAGCUUCAUGCCAUAGUAGAGCAUUUUCAGAAAACUGGUAAGCUCAGCUAAAGCUAAUAUGGCAUAUAUGGAUAGAACAUUUGAUGAGUAAAUUCCAGUUCUGAAAGUCUACUAGUCGCUGAAAUACUUAGAAUAAAAAAUGAGGAUUGAUUUUGUAUGUGUCAUGAAACAGUAGCAUUUCUAGGUCAGCAUUUUCCCAGCUGUGUUAUUCUUUCCUGUUUGUCAAUGCUCAGUGCAUCUUAGAGGUAGGAAAUUAUUCUACUGCUUGUGAAACUAGAACUAGAUAGCACAUAGUAAUAACACAGUGUGAAUAGUUAUUAGGACCUAUUAUAGCACUUUUCCUGUAGAACGCUCUAGCUGUUUUCUUCCAUAACAUGGGUCAAAUUGUGCCUCUCUUAAAUGGGAAGCACACAGGGAGAGGGUUCCAUCAGACAGAUGUAGGCUGCAUGACUAUCAAGAGGUGAGAAAUGGUUCAACUCAGCUGGCCAAGACCCACUCACACCCCUGAGACCCAGCCUAGCCAGAGAACAGCUGGCUGAUCUUGGCAGGAGUUUUAGGGCAGAUAGUUCAUCACCACAGCACCACUAAUCCAUUCAUUUUCUUUCUCAAUAUAAGGACCCUUGAGAAUGUUCCCAUCUCCCUUCUGUGCAUUUUUGCUGGCUUCCAUCCCUGGGGAAUCAGCCACAUUUUCUCAUGUGUCUUCAGGGCAUCUUAGGACAUAGGAAGGGGAAAGAAAUGAAAUUUUACCUUCAAAGAUGAGAAUGGAAGAGAGAAUAAAGGAAACUGUCCUGGACCUCACAGGCAAUAAACAAACAGUUAACUGAAGACUUCACUCUGAUUCAAUCCACUCUUCUUUUUAGUGAUCUGCCUAUCUGUGAUGUAUCUCCAGGCAAAAACUUUCAUAUACAGUAGUUUAAAAAUGAGCUGUUUCUUCCUGCAGGUCUGACUGCACAGGCAUAUUGAGCGAGGCAACUUGAACACCAGGCUGAGGCCGAUUUUGUGAAGCAUCUUUCACUCUUUCUCUUUUCUGGGGAUGUGGGACAGGUUGUGGGUGGGUGAGUGUGUGUGUAUGCUGGACUUCUUUGGAAGAUGUGGGACCCAAGAAGUAUCACUGUGAGAGUUUAAGGAGACAGUUAAUGACAUGUGUUUACAGCCAUUGUCACACAACAGCAUCUGUAAGAAGAUUGGACGUGAUUAUCUGGAUCUAGCUUGAAGUAGUCAAGGCAAAGAUAUAAUUGUGUAGUCUUGAAGCCAAAUAAAUCCCCAAAUGAACAAAACAACCCACAAUGAAUUAUAUCAUGUACUUUGCAAAGGUAGCUAAGCUUAGGGAAGACCCGGCACUGCACUAACCUCAUCUCUCUUGGUUAUUCACAAAAACAAUUUGAGUCUAAGGGCAAGGCACCUUUGUCAGUUGCCCAUUCCAUUACUAAUGUUGGACUUUCUUUUUCAUUCAAGCCUGACAAAAUGCUGCAACCUGACAUCCCAGCAGGCAGUUUUCACUAUUGUACUAACUACUCCAUCUGUUAUGAAGGUCACAAGAAUGUAUCUUGUUUUAAAUUUUUCUAUGGAGUGAUUUAUUGUCUUGGCUAUAAAUUUGUAAAGAAAUAAAACGCUAUUUCUUCAUCGUC